ACAUCCAGCUGCCUGAGACCCUCCUGCAGCCUUCUCAAGGGACAGCCCCACUCUGCCUCUUGCUCCUCCAGGGCAGCACCAUGCAGCCCCUGUGGCUCUGCUGGGCACUCUGGGUGUUGCCCCUGGCCAGCCCCGGGGCCGCCCUGACCGGGGAGCAGCUCCUGGGCAGCCUGCUGCGGCAGCUGCAGCUCAAAGAGGUGCCCACCCUGGACAGGGCCGACAUGGAGGAGCUGGUCAUCCCCACCCACGUGAGGGCCCAGUACGUGGCCCUGCUGCAGCGCAGCCACGGGGACCGCUCCCGCGGAAAGAGGUUCAGCCAGAGCUUCCGAGAGGUGGCCGGCAGGUUCCUGGCGUUGGAGGCCAGCACACACCUGCUGGUGUUCGGCAUGGAGCAGCGGCUGCCGCCCAACAGCGAGCUGGUGCAGGCCGUGCUGCGGCUCUUCCAGGAGCCGGUCCCCAAGGCCGCGCUGCACAGGCACGGGCGGCUGUCCCCGCGCAGCGCCCGGGCCCGGGUGACCGUCGAGUGGCUGCGCGUCCGCGACGACGGCUCCAACCGCACCUCCCUCAUCGACUCCAGGCUGGUGUCCGUCCACGAGAGCGGCUGGAAGGCCUUCGACGUGACCGAGGCCGUGAACUUCUGGCAGCAGCUGAGCCGGCCCCGGCAGCCGCUGCUGCUACAGGUGUCGGUGCAGAGGGAGCAUCUGGGCCCGCUGGCGUCCGGCGCCCACAAGCUGGUCCGCUUUGCCUCGCAGGGGGCGCCAGCCGGGCUUGGGGAGCCCCAGCUGGAGCUGCACACCCUGGACCUUGGGGACUAUGGAGCUCAGGGCGACUGUGACCCUGAAGCACCAAUGACCGAGGGCACCCGCUGCUGCCGCCAGGAGAUGUACAUUGACCUGCAGGGGAUGAAGUGGGCCGAGAACUGGGUGCUGGAGCCCCCGGGCUUCCUGGCUUAUGAGUGUGUGGGCACCUGCCGGCAGCCCCCGGAGGCCCUGGCCUUCAAGUGGCCGUUUCUGGGGCCUCGACAGUGCAUCGCCUCGGAGACUGACUCGCUGCCCAUGAUCGUCAGCAUCAAGGAGGGAGGCAGGACCAGGCCCCAGGUGGUCAGCCUGCCCAACAUGAGGGUGCAGAAGUGCAGCUGUGCCUCGGAUGGUGCGCUCGUGCCAAGGAGGCUCCAGCCAUAGGCGCCUAGUGUAGCCAUCGAGGGACUUGACUUGUGUGUGUUUCUGAAGUGUUCGAGGGUACCAGGAGAGCUGGCGAUGACUGAACUGCUGAUGGACAAAUGCUCUGUGCUCUCUAGUGAGCCCUGAAUUUGCUUCCUCUGACAAGUUACCUCACCUAAUUUUUGCUUCUCAGGAAUGAGAAUCUUUGGCCACUGGAGAGCCCUUGCUCAGUUUUCUCUAUUCUUAUUAUUCACUGCACUAUAUUCUAAGCACUUACAUGUGGAGAUACUGUAACCUGAGGGCAGAAAGCCCAAUGUGUCAUUGUUUACUUGUCCUGUCACUGGAUCUGGGCUAAAGUCCUCCACCACCACUCUGGACCUAAGACCUGGGGUUAAGUGUGGGUUGUGCAUCCCCAAUCCAGAUAAUAAAGACUUUGUAAAACAUGAAUAAAACACAUUUUAUUCUA